AGAAGAGCGCGGAGCACCGGAGGGCACGCAGCUGACGGAGCUGCGCUGCGUUCGCCUCGUUUGCCUCGCGCCCUCCACUGGAGCUGUUCGCGCCUCCCGGCUCCCACCGCAGCCCACCCGGCAGAGGAGUCGCUACCAGCGCCCAGUGCGCUCUGUCAGUCCGCAAACUCCUUGCCGCCCGCCCCGGGCUGGGCACCAAAUACCAGGCUACCAUGGUCUACAAGACUCUCUUCGCUCUUUGCAUCUUAACUGCAGUUCUAGAGAUUGGGAAGUCCAAGAUCAGGGCAUCUGCAGGUUCUGCGUCUGGAGGGGGCUGUCUUUCUGGUUCACUAGCUGUGUCUUCCUCAUGUGGUGGAAGGGGAUGGAGGGUACAGAGUCUGCCUACAUCAGCUCCUUUGUCUGUUUCUCUUCCGACAAACAUUGUACCACCGACCACCAUCUGGACUAGCUCUCCACAAAACACUGAUGCAGACACUGCCUCCCCAUCCAACGGCACUCACAACAACUCGGUGCUCCCAGUUACAGCAUCAGCCCCAACAUCUCUGCUUCCUAAGAACAUUUCCAUAGAGUCCAGAGAAGAGGAGAUCACCAGCCCAGGUUCGAAUUGGGAAGGCACAAACACAGACCCCUCACCUUCUGGGUUCUCGUCAACAAGCGGUGGAGUCCACUUAACAACCACGUUGGAGGAACACAGCUCGGGCACUCCUGAAGCAGGCGUGGCAGCUACACUGUCGCAGUCCGCUGCUGAGCCUCCCACACUCAUCUCCCCUCAAGCUCCAGCCUCAUCACCCUCAUCCCUAUCAACCUCACCACCUGAGGUCUUUUCUGCCUCCGUUACUACCAACCAUAGCUCCACUGUGACCAGCACCCAACCCACUGGAGCUCCAACUGCACCAGAGUCCCCGACAGAGGAGUCCAGCUCUGACCACACACCCACUUCACAUGCCACAGCUGAGCCAGUACCCCAGGAGAAAACACCCCCAACAACUGUGUCAGGCAAAGUGAUGUGUGAGCUCAUAGACAUGGAGACCACCACCACCUUUCCCAGGGUGAUCAUGCAGGAAGUAGAACAUGCAUUAAGUUCAGGCAGCAUCGCCGCCAUUACCGUGACAGUCAUUGCCGUGGUGCUGCUGGUGUUUGGAGUUGCAGCCUACCUAAAAAUCAGGCAUUCCUCCUAUGGAAGACUUUUGGACGACCAUGACUACGGGUCCUGGGGAAACUACAACAACCCUCUGUACGAUGACUCCUAACAAUGGAAUAUGGCCUGGGAUGAGGAUUAACUGUUCUUUAUUUAUAAGUGCUUAUCCAGUAGAAUUAAUAAGUACCUGAUGCGCAUUGAACGACAAUCUUAAGCCCUGUUUUGUUGGUAUGGUUGUUUUUGUUUUCCUCCCUCUCCUCUGGCUGCUACAACUUCCCCUUUCUGGUACAAGAAGAACCAUUCUUUAAAGGUGAGUGGAGGCUGAUUUGCAGCUGAAGUGGGCCAGCCUUGCACCAGCCAGGCCAGACCACCAUGGUGAAGGCUUCUUUCCCCACUGCAGGACCCACUUUGAGAAGGACCGAGGAGGAGGAUUUGGGUUGUUUUGUUAGGGGUUACUUUCAGGGGAACAUUUCAUUUGUGUUAUUUCUUAAACUUCUAUUUAGGAAAUUACAUUAAGUAUUAAUGAGGGGAAAGGAAAUGAGCUCUACGAGGAUUUCACCCUGCAUGGGAGAGAGCAGGGUUUUCUCAGAUUCCUUUUUAAUCUCUAUUUAUCUGGUUGUUUCUGACAGGAUGCUGCCUGCUUGGCUCUACAAGCUGGAAAGCAGCUUCUUAGCUGCCUAAUUAAUGAAAGAUGAAAAUAGGAAGUGCCCUGGAGGGGGCCAGCAGGUCACGGGGCAGAAUCUCUCAGGUUGCUGUGGGAUCUCAGUGUGCCCCUACCUGUUCUCCCCUCCAGGCCACCUGUCUCUGUAAAGGAUGUCUGCUCUGUUCAAAAGGCAGCUGGGAUCCCAGCCCACAAGUGAUCAGCAGAGUUGCAUUUCCAAAGAAAAAGGCUAUGAGAUGAGCUGAGUUAUAGAGAGAAAGGGAGAGGCAUGUACGGUGUGGGGAAGUGGAAGAGAAGCUGGCGGGGGAGAAGGAGGCUAACCUGCACUGAGUACUUCAUUAGGACAAGUGAGAAUCAGCUAUUGAUAAUGGCCAGAGAUAUCCACAGCUUGGAGGAGCCCAGAGACCGUUUGCUUUAUACCCACACAGCAACUGGUCCACUGCUUUACUGUCUGUUGGAUAAUGGCUGUAAAAUGUUUAAAAACAAAACAAAACAAAAAAGAGGCACUAGUCUAUCUGCAAUUACUCAACGAGGCAUUUUCAUAGGAAACAGACUAUGAUUAAUCCAUUUAUUCUUCCCACACACUUACCUUACUAAGUCUUUGCUUUAAUAAAUGAGCAACCCUGGGUAUAGUCUUAAAAUUCUGCACAAUAAAUUUUGAGAAAGAAUUGUUCCUCUUUGUAGGUAUCUGUGUAUUGCAAUCAUUCUCAACCAGGAGGUGAUUUUGCCCCCUGACUCCACCCCAGGGACAUUCAAAAAUGUCUGGUGACAGUUUUCAUUGUCAUGACUUGGGGGUGCUACUAGAAGCCAGGAAUGCUGCCAAACAUUCUACCAUGCACAGCACAACCUACAACAGCAAAGAAUCAUCCACCCCAAAAUAUCAGUAGUGCCGAGAUUGAGAAACCCUGAUUUAUCACAAUGCCCACUGUGACAGAACAAGACACUCACAGAUUAGUGAUACGUUUUAUUUUUAACAAAAUGAAAUGAUGUGUUAAGUUUUUAUUUCCAAAGUGUUUAGUUUAUUGGCUGAUGGGUUGUUCUUGGUAUGCAUGGUGACCUUUUUAUUUCUGUGUGCUUCCUAGAGAGCUUUAUUUCAUGGCGACAACUCUGUCUUCUUGUAACAGCUGAUAUUAGCAAGCAGCAUCUUAUGUCCUGAUUUCAUAUAGUAGAAAACAAACAUUGGGUCCGACUUCAAAAUGUGUUGUAUUGUCCUACAGUGUCAUAAAGAACCUGAAAAUGAACUUUUGUUUCUAAAGUUGGACCUUGCUGCCAUGACUGUUUAGUUUACAGAAACUUGACCCCGGCUCAUCCUGUCUCUGGCUGUGGCCCGGCAAAGCACUGAAAACCCCUCUGGUCUCAGAGACAGUAGGGGCAGUGCCACUUUCUACAACCUGCCAACCCACACACUGGAGUAAUUCUGAAAAAAAUUAUUCCUAAACUCUCUAAGUGUGGACGGAGAAUGAGCAAGCCCCAGAAGUAUUUUACAACCAGAGUGGGUAAUGAGGAGGGGGCUUACUGGAAUCGUCAUAUCUCUGAAUAUUGAAAACAACAACUAAAAAAGUGGACCUUCUCAGAAAAAAAGGGCAGCAAAUGACCAAGGGCGCCCCUUCUGGCCGUGCUUGGCUUGAGUAACUGUCUCUCUUUCCCCACCCCCAUCACAGGGCUUUCAGUUUGGCAAAGGAAAAGCAGAUAAAAACAGAACAUUCCAUAUGUUUCUUUCUCCAUCGGCCAAAAACAUUUUGACACAAUGUUUGUGAAACACCUUUGGAGAGGUGCACUUCUGAAUGCUGCCUCUGCCGUAAAUCCUGGGGCAAGGGAUCAGCCUCUUCCCAGGAACCAUCGCCUUCUAUAAACCGUGAACUCAAGCAGGCAUUUUUUUUUUCUUACCGAAAGGCUGCUAUUGUGCAAGGGCACAUAAUGGGUCUGUUGCUCUUAUUGGCUUCCAAAUGUGCAUGGCAAAGAGAGAGAUGUGGGCCUAGAGCAGAUAUAUUCAGCAAGGUGACAGCUUCCCAUAACAAUUCUAACACUUCUUAUCUUAUGUGAGAAUAAAAUAUUUAAGGGUUGAACCUUAUUUUGCCAAAUGUAUCUUUUCUGCUUUUGAAUUGGGCAGAAGAUUUUAGCAACUAUAUUCUACAAAUGUUACUUAUAACACACACACACACAUCUGAAAUAUAUGCCGAAAAUUGACGUCUUUGACCUCAGGGAGAGCACCUGUCCAGGUCUGCCUAAAGGAAAUGGCUCCAGUGGGUCUAAACAACCACAUCCUAUCCAUGGAUAGGUCUAGUCAUAACACUUUAGAGAGAAUGUCAGAGCAGGAGGGAGGCAAGCCGCCUCUUCUCGGCCAUCGACUGCAGAUGAUGAAAGAGCGGGAUUCAACUUUGUUUUCUUUUCCUGUGGCCCCAGUGAAACCUCCUGCCCUCCCUGCACGUCUGUGUCUUCAUUUCUAAAAUGGGGGUGAUGCUUUCAUAUUGACCUCACCCCAUACUACCUCACAGAUGUGUUGUGAGGAUUAAUAAAAUUAUGUCUAUGGUAUUUUCAGUUUCUGGAGAAAAAUACUUAUAGACAGUUUAACUAUUACAUAGAUAUAUAAGUGAUCUCAGUUUCUUGUUUGCUGUGAUACUAAUGUGUUGUUUUAACUUAUUCCAUAAAAUGACAGUUGUGUCCUAGCCACAUCAGACAGCUAUCUAAGCUCUGGACUACCCCUUUGUGCAGCUGAAUCACUGCAGGGUUGACCAUGCCUGGUGCCACAGCCAUGGUUUCCAUUUCUAGAUGAAAGGAUGGCCUAGGACAUAGGUCUCAAAGACUCUUGGAUCAGAAUCAGGAGAUUAGGGAAAACAGGAUGGAUACCUGAGCACUAACAGCAGUAGACGUAGACCUCUGUCCUUUACCAUCUGAGGUCUUCUGGAUUCUUUGUGGGGUUAAUUUUGAUUUGAUGUCAUCUGUUUGCCCUUCAUCUUGCUUGCAAGUGUGCAUGGUUCAAUCCCUCACAUCCAGGAAAUGAAUUUUGCAAUUGGGCCAGAUGCUAAUUUGCACGUUGAUUCACCUUCUUUGCCUUUAAGCCUUUUUUUUCUUUUUUUUUUUUUUGGCAAAUGAAUGUACCAUUUCAACUUUGAUUUUAAUAGUGCUAGUUGAUAUUGGUAAUAAUGCUAACCAAGAGAUCAAUGCCAGAUUUUUCUCUUGGGGUAAGUUAGCUGAAGUCAUUUAAAGAUGGAAAGGUGGGAAAAUUCUUUGAUAUUUGAUGUCAUUGUAUCCACAUUUGUUGUAAGACAUAUUGCAUACCAAUUAUAAUUAUAUCAAUUAAAGUUGAUAAAAGCUUC